GUCCACCAUGGGUGAAUUAUGAAUCAGUAGCUAUGCCAGGCCUCAGCUGGGCCACAUCUGGAGAACUGGGGUGAGGGCACAACAUCACAAAAUAUCUGGCCCCAGUCUGGUCACUCAUCCCUUUUAGGGCAACAAGGAAACUAUCCUGUGGCCUGAGAGCACAAUACCUGAGACAAAGGCCAGCAGAAACAUUUGUCUGCCCUCACCCUUUCUGCCCCAGCUUCCACCUGCUCCCCAUCUGCCCACCCACUAAAGCCCAUGUGGCAUGCCAUCUCUCGAACAUCCAGGAUGUCCCAGAGUGGAUGUCCAUCAGGUCUGCUGGCAGACAAAAAUAUCUCUUCAAGUGCCACUCGAGUGAUAGUGAAGACUGCAGGCAACCAGAAAGACUUUAUGGUAGCUGAUGACAUCUCGGUAAGGCAGUUCAAGGAGAUGCUAUUGGCUCACUUCCAAUGCCAGAUGGACCAACUAGUGCUGGUCUUCAUGGGUUGCCUUCUCAAAGACCAUGACACACUGAGCCAGAGGGGCAUCAUGGAUGGCCACACCAUCUACUUGGUCAUCAAGUCCAAGCAGGGCUCCAGAUCUCUAGCCCAUUCCUUCCGGGACCUGCCAACGAAUGAUCCCUGCCACCGGGACAGAAACACCAAAGGAAACAGCAGCAGAGUGCACCAACCAACUGGUAUGAAUCAAGCUCCAGUGGAACUGGCCCACUUUGUGGGGUCUGAUGCACCCAAAGUGCAUACCCAAAACUUGGAAGUGAGCCACCCAGAGUGCAAAGCACAGAUGCUGGAGAAUCCUAGCAUCCAGCGGCUUCUGUCCAACAUGGAGUUCAUGUGGCAGUUCAUUUCAGAACAUCUAGACACGCAACAAUUGAUGCAGCAGAACCCAGAAGUUUCCCGCCUUCUUCUUGAUAAUUCUGAGAUCCUAUUGCAGACUCUGGAGCUGGCCAGGAACCUUGCUAUGAUCCAAGAGAUAAUGCAGAUCCAACAACCUUCACAAAACCUUGAGUAUCCACUGAACCCACAGCCAUAUCUGGGCUUAGAGACAAUGCCAGGUGGGAAUAAUGCCCUGGGUCAGAACUAUGCUGAUAUCAAUGAUCAAAUGCUGAACAGCAUGCAAGAUCCUUUUGGAGGAAACCCUUUCACAGCUCUCCUGGCAGGACAAGUGCUAGAACAAGUCCAGUCUUCACCCCCACCUCCACCACCAUCACAGGAACAACAAGACCAGCUCACACAGCAUCCUGCAACCCGAGUCAUCUAUAAUAGCUCUGGUGGUUUCUCUUCAAACACCUCAGCCAAUGACACCCUUAACAAGGUCAACCACACUUCCAAAGCCAACACUGCUAUGAUUUCCACCAAGGGCCAGAGCCAUAUCUGUGCCACUCGGCAGCCAGCUUGGAUACCAGCCUUACCUAGCAUAGAGCUUACCCAGCAGCUUCAAGAAGAAUACAAGGAUGCCACUGUUUCUCUAAGUAGCUCCAGACAGACAUUAAAGGGUGAUCUCCAGCUGUCAGAUGAGCAGAGCAGCUCCCAGAUCACAGGAGGCAUGAUGCAGUUGCUUAUGAACAACCCCUACCUGGCAGCUCAGAUUAUGUUGUUCACAAGUAUGCCCCAGCUGAGUGAACAGUGGAGGCAGCAGCUGCCCACAUUCCUGCAGCAGACACAGAUUUCUGAUCUGCUUAGUGCUUAGGCAACCCUAAAGCAUUCCAAGCAAUAUUGCAGAUUGAGCAGGCCCUCCAGCUGCUGGCCACAGAGGCUCCUGUUCUUCUGCCUUGGGUUGCACCCUACCUAUGGGGCCUGGGUUGGCUUCCUGCCCCCAGCUGCAGCUAUCCUGACACAGUGCCCUGUUCCUGGAAUGUUUCAGAUACAGCUGAGCCCAAGGGACCUGAGUGCUGCCACAAGCCUGGAACAGUCCUGCAGAGGCUACAAUCCCCGGAUGGGGACCCUUCCCACCCUCUGCAAGCUCCUGAGAUUUGUUUUAGCAAACAGAUGGAUUCUCUCCAGGCCAUGGGAUUUGGGAACCACCAUGCCAAUCUACAGGCACUCAUUGCUACUGAAGGGGACACCAAUGCUGCUAUCCGCAAGCUCAAGAGAUCCCAGAGAUUCUAACCACCAUGCCUACUUGUUUGCUUGCUACCUGCCUGCUGACCCACCUGACCAUCUCAUUUGCCUUUUGCACCUUUCCUGAUGCUUCCAGCCAGGAGAAGUCCUGGAAUAAGAGUUAUCAACCAAUGUGUCUUGUACUGAAUAAUAGAUCAUUGGUCGUGGCUGAAACAUCUGUCAAUAAAAUGGCUACACUCACUUGCUGCGA